ACUGGGGUACUGAAUAUAAUACGUAAAGGGGGUAAAAAAGAUCCUGCAGCCAAGAAAAUUGAAAACCACAGAGGAACAUAAAGGGAGUGUCAGGAGAUGGUUGAAAGAGUAGUUUGAGGCCACCUUUGAAGGGCCAAGUGGUUGAUGUUUGCCAGAGAAAAGCCAGCAGUUCUGACCAGGGUUACUUUAAAAUUUGCCACAAAUCUCAAAUGACACUCGACCCGGAAGUGUUACUGCCUCCUUUAAUAUGUUCUCCACUCUCUGAAGUCAUUUCUUCCUUUUCACUUCUCCUUGAACUUCACCUAGUGUCCUGUCCCCCACUUCCCCCACCCCGUCCUUCCCUCAGCAUAUAACCUCAUUUAGAAAGCAUUGAACAAAUAGAAGCCGUCAGCUUCCACUCUUCCCACCAUCCCAUCUAAAUUUUGGACAGCUGGGUCCGUCAGUCUACAGACAUGCUGGAGGGGCUGCCCUGCCUGGUUUUGUAGCUGCUAGCUAUAUAUGGCAAUUUAAAUUUCAGCUAAUAAAACUUAAAAUUCAGUUUCUCAUAUCAAGUGCUCACUAGCCACAUGUGGUUAGUGGUUACUGGAUUGAACAGUGCAGAUAUAGACGAUUCCCACCAUUGCAGUGUCUUCCACUGACAUGGCUCACCAUUCCGGGGCCGCCCAUCUUGAAAGCAAAAUAAACUACAGUAACAGCAGAAGCUCUCCUUCACCCUUAGUCUCUCAUUUUAGUGUCUUCUCGUGUUUUCUGUUCCUUUUUUUUUUUUUUUUUUUUCAGAUGAGGUCUUGCUUUUUGGCCUGGGCUGGAGUGCAUGGUGCAAUCAUGGCUCACUGCUGCCUCAAACUCCUGGUCUCAAGCAGUCCUGCUUCAGACUCCCUAAGUGCUGGGAUUAUACAUGUGAGCUACCACACCUGCCCUGUUCCUUUUCAUAGCAGGAGUGAAAAGCCUUGUCUAAAGCUGAGGUCUCCUAUUUCUAUAGAGACACCGUACCUGGCAACCGUCAACUUACCUGCGAUGAUCUCCUUAACUUACCCCAAUCUAGCUUUCACCUCCAGCACACCUAGGAAACUGCUCAAGUCAGCAUCACUGGCAGUGCUAACAUUUUCAAAUGCAGGGGGCUCCUUUUUUUUUGUCUCUUGUUUUCCUUCUGCUUCACUAGCCACUCCUUAGGUGCAGGCUCCUCUUUUGCUCAGUCUGGAAAUGUUGGAAUGCCCCAGGCCUGUGUCCAGGAUCAUCUUCUACAAUUACAUUUACUUUACCUACAUGAUUUCAUUUAGUCUCAUGGCUUUUUAUACCAUUUUACAGUCAUGAUUGAGAAAUUUUUAACUUCAGCUCUAACUUUCCUCUUGGGCUCUAUAUGCAGUUUCUUACCAGGUAUCUUCACAUGAAUAACUAAUAGACAUCUCAGAUGUCCCAAGCAGGCCUCUUGAUUUCCUCCCUGCACUCUGCCCCGUCCCCUGUCAUAACUUAAACUGGCCUCUUCCCGUCUCAGAAAAUGGACCACCAUAGACCCAGGUGCUCAAGCUUAAACGUAGGGAGCAACCUUGAUUAUGCUUUUUUCUCCCCACUCCUUCUCCACAUCCAAUUUUUGAGUCCCGAAUCCACAUGCUUUCUAUUUGAAUCUUCUUUCUCAGGAACACUGUGGUAGCCUCCUGUUUGGUCUCCCGGCAUUCAGUUUUGCCCUGUUUCAGUCCACCUUGUCUGCAGCAGUGGCAGAGGAAUCUUGCUAAACUGUAGAUGAUUUCAUGUCAUGUCCUCAGUUAAACCUUCCAAAGGCUUUACAUUGCAUUUAGAAUAAAAUCCAAACCUUUUCUGACCUGCAGGAUCUUACUGGCCUGGGCCCCACUUUCCUCCUUGCCCUCAUCCCAUAACACCCUCUUCAUGAUUCCUAUGUUCCAGCUGCCCUGCGCUUUUUCUGUUCCUAAAGGCAAGCUCAGAGCAGCCACAGUUCUUCAGUCUUUAUUUUUCUCUUCGUCGGGAAUGUUUUUCCCUCUUUUAUUUAUUUAUUUUUUUAUUUGAGACAAGGUCUCGCUCUGUUACCUGGGCUGGAGUGCAGUGGCAUGGUCAUAGCUCACUGCAGCCUUGAAGUCCUGGGCUCAAGCAAUCCUCCUGCCUCAGCCUCCUAUGUAGCUGGGACUACAGGUGUGCACCACCAUGCCUGGAUAAUUUUUAUAAUUUUUGUAAGAGAUGGGGGGUCUCGCUGUGUUGCCCAGGCUGGUCUUCAACUCUUGGCCUCAAGUAAUCCUCCUGCCUCAGCCUCCCUAGGUGCUGGGAUUAGAGGCAUGAACCACCAUGCCCAGCCUGCCCUCAGAUCUUUGGAUGGUUGGCUCCUAUUAGUUAUUUUAGUCUCUUAGCUAAGGGGUUGCCUUCUCAGAUGGCCUCUCUGACCUCCUAAGCUAAGGGAGCCCCUCCACUAUCAUACUGUUAUUUUCUCUGUGACACUUAACACUGUUUGAAACUGAGUUGUGUACAUUUUUAUUGCUUAUCUCCCUCAACUAGAACAAUAAGUUUCAUAGCAACUGAGACUUUUUCCUAUUUACUAGGUGUAUCCCUGCAUCUAGAACAGUGUGUUUAGAUAGUAGGUGCUCAGUACAUAUUGUUGAAUGAAUGAGUGGGGCUGGGAUUCUAAACCGUAGGCCAUUAGUUCUCAGGUGGUAUACCAUGAGGCCUCCCAUAUUCAAUUUUCAUAAACAUAGAAAGUUGACUUUUGUUAUAAUCAAGCAUAGAGCAUUUUAGAGCAUUUUGCUGAGCGGGUUGUGCAGUGUGUUAGAGAGUGGGGAAAAACUUGCUGCAAAUUGGUGAUAAGAGGUAUGGGGUAACUGCAAGCCAGUGCCAAAGAAAGAGGUUAUGUUUACAGCAGCAUGCAAGAACUGUGUCUUGUGAACACGACAGAAAAGGUUCAGAAAGUAAACAACUUCUUUCAAACAGUGUCAGAUGUUGAAGGGCCGCCAAGUGAACUGCGUGAAGACUAUGAAUGCAUUUCUAAGUAAUCUGAGAUAUUAUGUUAGAAGAGUGUGCUGCAGUGUUAUUACUGACUUGUUCUUUUAAUGGCUUCAGACAUGCCUCUAAAAAUUGUAGUAUUCAGAAGUGUACCAUAAGUUAAAUUUAAGAUUGCAUAAACAUUGUAAGAAUAGGGAUAAUGUCAGUAUCUCAGUCCUUUGUGGGUCUUUUUCUAUUGUGUAUUGUUUCUGCUGGUUCUUCUUCAUGGUGCCUUGUUGCCAUUUAUGUUUGGUUCAUUUUGGCUCUGAGCUGCUCACUUCCUUGGAUAGUCAUUCAGGGAACAUUCUUCAAGUCUUAAGAUAAAGAUGUAUCCUUCCAGAGAGAAUUGUUUGUUUUUGCCACAUGGCUAGGGAUACUGGAGACCAAGACCAUUUGAAACUAAAUUCACAGCUUGGAAUUUUUUGGACCUCAUGGUGAUAUAAAAUUGGGCUGCAGUCCCUGGGGUGGCAUGGUUUUAUUUUUGGUAGACCCAUUGUAGCCUUAUGGAGAAAAGGUUUCCUAUUAGACUUCACACCUUGGGUGGGCCCUAGUCUUUGUCUUCUGUUCCUGUCAACCCAUGAGGCCAUCAAAGCCCUUAGAGCCAAAGUGGCUUCCAUGACUAACUUAUUCUUCCUGCUUCCAGUUUUCACUAAGAUCUUGACAGGCCGACUUCUCUCCUCCCUCUUCCAACUCUUUCAUGCCUUCAAGAAGAUGUUUAAGAACAUAUUUUAUUCAGGACGCUUACUUAUUUUCAGUGCAGAGCUGACCUGAAUAACCCUGUCAGCAGAAAUGCAAAUCAACCUCAAAGUUUCAAAAGAGGGAAUCCAACAGUAAGUGAGACAGUGAGAAGCCAAAGCAUGGUGGCACUUCUGCAGCCUUCCAGGGAUGGAUCUGUGAGGGGAGUCAGUGGGACAGGAGGUGGGACUGCAAGAAGGAAGAAUGCCAUUUCUGUCUUCCAGAGGUGAUGGGAACCUGAGCUUGGGCAGGGGUAACAGACAUUGUUGGAUAACCAGGUAUAGAUGUGGUAGAAGCUGUGUUGUCUAAGUGGCCCAUAGCCUAAAAGGUUUGAAGAUACUGCUGUAAACAAGCAGACAAAGGAUGUGCUUAGAGAGAUUUCAGGUAGAAUCAGCUGGAUUUGGUGACUGUUAGGUAACAGGAAGGAAUCGACAGUGACUCACCUAGGUCAUUUUCUUACCAUUCACACUCUCCAUUACAUUAUUGUUAUUUGGGGGCUGUUAGCUUCUGGCGGGAUACCCCUGCCCCUCUUGCCACAACUGGGAUUGUACACACAGAUACUGUGAGACAGAAGAGGAUUAAUAAACUGCCCUGGGAGAGUUAGUGGUAGGCUCUUGAAAUUCUUCAAGAAUUGAAUUAGCGUGGUGGAUGGAGAAGCUGGAGAAAACAUGUUACAGGCAGAGUAAUGCAUAGAAAAGCAUAAAGGGUAUGUGGCAUUUCCAGGGAACUGCCAAACCCUUCUUCAGGUGCUUCUAUACUUCUCUCCUUCUGAUUUUAUGGUUUUAUUCAUUUCCAUUCUUAUGGACAUGUUCUUAUUUAAAUUACUUUUGUUUGUGUUUCUGUAGGCUUGGUCAUUUAGGCUUAGAAACAUAUUUGCAAGUUGCUAGACACCCUAACAUUCAGAGCUUAGUUUAUUUGUAGUUGUAAUAAAUAAGCCUUGCUUUUGUUUUUUCAGCCUGGACUUUGAGGAAGGUGUUAGGUAUUAGUCAACCCGAGAAUGACCUCUGUAGCAUUCUACAUGACCUGCACAAAGGCUCCAGGUGGUAGGGGCAGGUGGGGGCUGACGUCAGUAUUGCCACCUGCACACCAUAGCAAGGGGCUGCAUUAGCGGGAGACAGGCACCCUUUUUGUGAGUUGUCCGCACAGAGGAGGCUCAUUUUCUGAUGUGCACAGAGGUGCCUGUGUGCUAGCAGCUGCCCUGGUUUGCCUUGCUUUUCUCGGGUCAUGCAUCCAAAAUUUCUCAUGUCACGUUCCCAAGCACUGGUGUCUUUGGAGGAGCGUUCAGGUGGUGUUCAGUCUGGACAGAAGAAAAGAAAGUGGGGUUUAUAAAGUCCCCUUAUAGAUUUGAAUCUGCUUUAGAAAAUGCACCGUUGUGCAGUCUUUGCUGCUGCUACAUACAUGCUUCUAUAAUGCAGAUUCACUUGUAUGAGAUCGGUGCUAUCGGGAAUGUGGUGUAGGAUGUAUGAAUUGGUCCAUAAGCAGUUUUCCUUGAGUAUGCCACUGCCUCCAAGUAUCAGCAGCUAGGUGCAAAGUACACUAAUACAGCUCAAGGCAGCAAGCCAAAUUGAGAAACAGGACUGCAUACCUUGCUCUUGUAUCCGUUUUCUUCCUCCUGACUCCAGCAGGCUUCUGCUCGAUCUCAGAAGUACUCAUUUCAGGGUUCUCUCCAAUCUCUGGACAUUUUCUCCUAGUCUGUGUAACUUAGAAGCUUGGUUACUCCUUGUAUUCCUUCCAUCAAAUGAUCCUCACCUUUGUGUUUCUAAAGUCCAUUAUAUAUCUAUUAGAAAUUACACUAAAAUACUGUUUAUUUUUCUAUUUUUAGGAUUUUUAUUUUUAAGCAUUCUGGUGAUAGAGUUUCAUAGUUUUUCAGUGGUCUGCCUAAAAUCUGGAUUUUAGUGUCUAUGUAGAACUUAGAAAUUUUUCAGAAAUACAUAUAUUGCAUUACAAUAAAAGUGUUUGUAUUUACAAUGUAUUUUGAACAACUAUAUGCCCAGGCUGCAAGUUUCCCAAAGAAAGAUGUAAUCGUUGGUUUUUUUGUUUCCAAGGAUAACCAGGUAUAGAUGUGGUAGAAGCUGUGUUGUCUAAGUGGCCCGUAGCCUAAAAGGUUUGAAGAUACUGCUCUAAACAAGCAGAACAUUAAUUUAUUUGUCGGCCCUUUGAGUUUUCUUACUAAUCCUCUUCUGGCCUGACCAUGUGCCCCUCCCAAGUUUCGCACAUUCCCAGGUAUCUAGUGUGUUCAGUUGUCUCCCUGCGCUACUCAGCAGCUACCUUUUUCAGCAUUGGCCCUAGCUUGCUUCUGUGCCCAGGAACAGGAACAGAAGUUUUCUUCUCAGGGGUCCCCUGUCUCUCUUAGACCAAGUCCACAGGCUUUUACUACAUUAGGCCUUGGAGUACAUUUCCUGUAGAAUCAAAGGGCCAACUUACAAAUGAAUGUUUGGAACACAACCCAUUCAUAAAUUAGGUUCUGCCUGCACCCAGAUGGAAAGUUAAAUGCUUUGGCAUCAGAAGAACUGUUGGGAAACAGAUAUUGUUUCUGAAAUUAUGAUAAAUCCAUAAGGCACUUUCUUUUUGGCACGUUGCGCCAAAGUAGGAGGACAGGAGCAAAUUUUAGGGACAUUAAAAAAAUAGGUUAGGAGAAGCUAAUCUUUUUGUCUAAUUCACUUUCUCUUGCAGUUCUGGCAUCGGAUACUCACAGAUUUAACACAUGCCAAUGAAUAUUUGAGCCAGGAAAUAGCCAAUAGUGAAUAUUUUUAUUAUGUGUUAGAUAAAGCUUCUUUCUUCUUAUGCUUAUUUAGGUGAACUAGAAAUAUGGUUUCAGUGAAAUUUAAGUUCUGAUAAGUACAGAUACAUAGCAUAUUUUCUGAAAAAUUUGAAAAACACACACAAAUAUAAAAAAUUACCAUAACCAUUCUAUCAAGCAACCAGUGUUAAUGUUUUAAUGUUUCUUUCCAAUGUCUUUUUAAAAAAAUCUCAUUGAGACUAUUCUAUGUAUUUAAUCUUACUAUGUAUUCUUAACAAUUAUUUUAAAUUUUUGAUCACUGCUUAAUAAUUAGGUUGGUGCAAAAGUAAUUGUGGUUGUUGCCAUUACUUUCAGUGGCAAAAACUGCUAUUCCUUUUGCACCAACCUAAAUAGUUUAAUGAAGUUUAAUAGUCCAAACAUUGGUCCCAGUAUUUUGCCACCACAAAUAAUGUUGCUGUCAGCAUCUCCCUGUAUGAAACUCUUUCUUAUUUAGGAUGAUUUCCUUAGAAGAGAUUCUCUUUUUGGGGAAUUUACUUGGUCAAAGGGUAUGAAUAUUUUAAGGCUCUUGGUACAUGUUGCCAAGUUGCUUUCAAAAAGGGUUAUACCAGAUUAUAACCCUAGCAGUGUGGCUAAGAGCUGCUUUCCCACAUCUUCUGCUUUCAGGGUUCUAAAUUGAACAGCAAAGAUUGGAAUAAAAAGAUAUCCUUUUUUCCCAUAUGCUUUUAACCCAUUUAAAUCUCUUUAUAGAGAUUUUCAGCAGUUUGACCAAAGAUGUACGCACAUGGGCAGUGUGGGAGUAUCAGGUCUGAGGUUGGAAGAUGGCUUCCACAUAGGCUGCCUGGCCCGAGUCUGCCCUCUGAAAAGAGCUGCUUUCAACUGACCCACUUCUCCCAGUUUUUCUUCGUCGGACUCUAAGCAGAGAGUGCCUGCAUCCCAGAAGCAGGUCGCUGUCCACUGUCUGUGGUUGGUUAAUUUUUGCUGGCCAUAGCCCACAUGAUUUAUAUUAAACUCAAUCCAAUAGCAUUUAAUGGCAGGCAGAAUUCUUCCCAUGUAAGUAGACUAGUCAGGAAUUUGCCUUUCAUUAUCCUCGGUCUGACUGCUUAACGUUAGACUCGACCUAUGGACGAUUCACAUGAACCGUUUCAGAAAAUGUAAUGUGACAUCUGCUAGAGUCCACAAUUACAGGGUGUGUGUGUGUUUGUGUGUGUGUGUGUAUGUGUGUGUUUAAUUUUUUAAAAAAUUUUCCGAGAUGCAGUUUUGCCCUGUUACCCAGGCUGGAGUACAGUGGUGUGAUCAUAGCUCACUACAGCCUCGAAUUCUUGGGUACAAGUGAUUCUCCUGCUUCAGCCUCCUGUAAUAGCUGGGACUAUAGUUGUGUGCCACCAUACCCCGCUAAUUUUUAAAAACAAAUUUUUGUAGAGAUGGGGGUCUUGCUGUGUUGCCUAGUAGGAUAGUCUUGAACUCCUGGGCUCAAGUGAUCUUUCUGCCUCGGCCUCCUAAAGUUUUGGGAUUUCAGACAUGAGCCACCACACCCAGCCUUGCUUUUUAAAUGUUGGAUGUUACCAUCCCUCUACUGUGGUCCUGUAGUUUGGCUUGAAGCUUGAUUCUGUGCGCUAGCCACUCUGUCAAGAAUUAUGUAGUAUAAAUAAUGCCGGUCACUUGUGCUGACCUCACAAACAUUCCGAAGCCUGGCAAGGCAGGUGUGGAAGCUCAGAGCUUUGCCAUCUAACUGAGUACUCAGGCUUCUUUCCAUUUAGAUAAGACACUCAGAAAGGAAAAGCAAUGCAAUUUUAAUUUUUACUUAACAUACAAAGUAGCCUUUUUUUUUUUUUUAAGCUGAAGGAAAUGAACUCCAGAGAACACUGAAGAAAAUUGAAGGAAAAAAGUAGAGCUCUUAGAAAGAAAGGAAAGGUCACGCUUAUAAACUGUAGCCAUCUAGAUAAACUGUUAUUUCCACUUUAUGUGGAUGUAUUUUAUUGUGACAGUGCUAACUACAGUUGCCAAUUUUCAGGAGGCCUAAAUUACUGACUAUUUUAGAUGAAUUCAGGCUUUAAAAUUAGCCCUGGGAUAAUAUAUUUCUUUUAAAAUGGGACCUUAAUUGAUCCUUAUUUUUUAAAGCUUGAAUUAAGUAGAAAAUUAAGGGUCUUUUGUAAAAGAUGAUAAUAUAUAUUUAACUUGGAUGAUUACCUAAUAGAGAAUUAUUCCUUGUUCUAGUAUUUUAAAAUAUUAAAUGUUUGACACAAAAACAGACCAUUCUGAAUAGGCUUUAGGAAGUAGGUGACUUUUCAGUAUGAAUAAACUAUAUGUAAUUUUUCAUUAACUUCAAAAUAAGAACUUUAAAAAUUAUGGAUAUAAAUUUUUAUGCCCUAUUUUAAGAAACUACCCUUUUUUUCUUAUGAGAAAAAUGUCUGCAAGAUUGAAAAAAGCUUCCAUAUAGAGUAAUACAUUGAAUGAAAUGAGUUGUUUUCUACUUAAUCAGAGUGGCCAAAGGCUAUUUCAAAACAAAUUUAUUCCCAUUUCUGAACCUUCAAAUCAAGAGACCAUUUAAGGAUUCAUUUCAAUUUGGUUAUUUAUAAGAAGAAAAGACUAUUCUGAUGGCAUGUAGGAUGGUCCUAAAGUAAUCGGCUCAGCUAAAAACACACUUAUAACAGUUGGGCAUGUCAGCUGAGGAGAGACCCUUAUAGCCUGUGUUUCCUACAAAAACAAAAACACAGUUCUUUUAUGAAAGUAGACAAGUUGAUGGUAUAUUUGGGCUAAAUAAAAUACAAUGUUGACAUAUGUUGAAAUAUUCUAUAGUUGUUACACAUGUUGGCUGAGGUGGUUGUACUGAUCCAGACACAUGGCUGAUACUUUGAGUGGGAACAUAGCCAGUGUGGUUUUAAAAUAUUAUGUCCCUCUGAGGAGGGAUUACAGAUGAUUUUUUGCUUUCUACUUACACCUUUUUAUAGGUUUCUUACAAAAAUAUUGCGCAUGCAGUCUUCUUACAAUUAGGGAAAAAACCCAAGACAUGCUCUAAGGUGAGAUGAGUGGGGGGAAGAAAUCUGUAUACAGUCAGCCCUCUGUAUCCAAGGCUUCUGAAUCUUCAGAUUCAACCAACCACGGGUCGAAAAUAUUAAAGGAAAAAAAUGAAAAAUAAUAUAAGUAAAAGCACCAAUACAGUAAAACAGCUACUUACUGUGACCAUACAUUGUGUUAGGUACUUACACAUGGACUAGAGAUGAUAUAGAGUAUAUGGGAGGAUGUGUGCAGGUUUUAUACAAAUACAAUGUUUUGUAUUAGGGACUUGAGCAUCUGGGGAGUGUGGUAUCCUGGGGAGUCCUGGAACCAAUCCCCCAAAGAUACCAAGGGAAGACUGUAUAUUGAAUUCAGUGAGGCAGAAAUGACUUGUACAUUUUGGUUUGUGAAAUAAAAUAUUCUCUUCAUAUAGGGGAUUUUUCUCUCUGUGUAGCUCUCCUAGGAAAUCCCUUGAUUAAAAGAAAUAUUGAUUGUACUGGGAGAAACAAAUAAUAAAUGAUUCUAAAAGUUGUCACUUUUUGUGAGUUUGGGAAAAACAAGGAUAAACUGCAGUGAUGACCACUAAUUUACCUACAGGUAUCCAAGUUUUUAUUGCAUCUUAGCAGUGAAAAAAAUCGGAGCAUGUGCUCUCAAUAUAUGAAUUUUUAUUUAUAAGUUUUCCUGUGUGUACUACUGAAUUAUUUUGUCUUAUACAUAGAAGUUUUAAAAGGAUCCACUGACGGUAAAUAUUAGUAACUAAAACUUGUUUUGUUAAAAAUUAUUGAUAGCGUGAAAAAUUAUCAUUAGUGUGUAGUGGAUUUUAUUUUUUCAAAUGAAGGUUAUGUGGAUGAGUUUGUAUCACUGUUUUUAAAAAUGGUGAAUAUUUUAUGAUAAAGCAAUUUGAAGGUCUGGUCCUAUAUUCAUUUUGCUAUUUGGUUUUAAUAGCUCAAAAAGUUACCUACAAAGAUACACGGAUCCAAAUGGGUGAAGUGCAUUGUUGACUGUGCUUUCUAACUGGUGAUUCUCAUUUUCACACUGUCCACCAGUUAGAUAAAAAUUUUUCUGGUAAAUUUCCAUUUUUGUGGAUAGCAGUAAGUUCUCAUAAAAUGUGUUCCAGUUUAUGUUAAGGAUAAAGAGGGUUGAAAAUAAAAAACUUUUUACAUUUAUUGAAAAUUUUAAAACAGAUGAGAAGUAUUUUAUAAGUUCUUUGUACAAAAGAUACAAAAGCACAUCUCUUUUCAAAAUACUUUCUGUACAGUCUGAGUUUCUUUUCAAAAAAGCAGUUAUUUUCUUGCACUUCUUAAAACCUCAUCUUUACCUUGAAGGGACUGAUUAAGUAAGGUCAUUGAAAAAAACAUCUGCCAGGUAUUACUGACAGCCACUUGUGAUCACAGAGUAGGUCAGGAAAUUUGGAGCAAAUUGUAUUUAUGUAAGGGAAAAAUGUGUUAAUCAUUCUUAAAACAAUUCUUCUAUGUAUUUUGCCACAAGAGAACUGGAACACCUCUGUAUGGUACAAAACAUUUUUGGGGUCACGCCCCACCUCAUUACUGAAAGGCUUUGUUUUUUAUACUACAUAGAUGGUAGCCCUACAUGAAUAAAUUGAACAGAUGACAGAGGGACCCACUGCCACAUCUUGAGUUAUUUAAGUGGCAUGUGACAUCUAACCUGUGGACCCAAAUAAGGGCUGUCAGUGUUGGUAAAAGCUGCAUUUCUUAGCUUUUAAGGUAAAAUUAAGUGUAAGUAGACAUUCUGACAGUUUCUUCUUGCACUCAGUAGAUUGUCUUGCUUACCCCUCGCCUAUACACAUCACUUAGAUUUUCAGGUACAGUAACCCCUUGGUAUCCCCAGGGGAUUGGUACUAGGAUCCUGCAGACACCAAAAUCCUCAGAUGCUCAAGGCCUUGCAGUCAGCCCUGUGGCACCCAGGGGUAUGAAAAGGUAGUCCGCCGUAUCCAUGGGCUCUGCAUCCAGCCAGUAAUGUAUUUUUGAAUCGCCUUUGCUUUAAUCCGAGGGCUCCGCAUACUCAGAUAAGGUGUGUAAAUGAAGGAGAGAGUGACUCUGGACUUAACACCUCUUUUAUCAUGCUCUCUUCAUUUCUUGGAUUCCAUUAAAAAAAAUCAUAACCCAUCAGAACCAGAUGGUAGUUGUAAUUUUUUUUUUCCUAAUCCCUUCAUGUUAUAGCUGAGAAAGCUGAGACAGUAAAAUAAAGAAACAGUGCUCAGUGAUAGAGCGAGGACCAGAAUUAUGUCUCCCAACGCAGCACCAGGCUGGGUGUGUGUGUUAAGGUCAUCUGUGGGUAGUGUGUCGAUGACUAAGCUCCCCAGAUGGGAACUAGUGGAGAUCUGUUGAUAUCUGACUUUCUAAAAACUAAUUUCUCUCUCAGAUCUCUCGGCUCUGUUCUUUUGUUUCUUAAACAUACGGCCUUGAAAUCAUCUUUAGUUUUUGUCUUUUUGCUUUCUUAUAGACACAUGCUUUGUCUAGCUAUUACUGAAACAUAAAGAAUACUCAUAAAUAGAUUCUCAUUUCCUGAGAAGUUGCCUUCUGAGUGAAUCAACAUGCCAUGUAGAAUCACUCUUGGACUCUUUUUAGUGAUGAUGGUGAAAUCCUUGUAUGUAUUACUCUCCAAAAGCCUUAAAAAUGUUAACAAAGAAUACAUAGGUAAAAUAAAGCAAAAUGCAAUCAGCUAAAAAAAAAAUGAAGUUGUAAAGAUGGGGAGAGAAAAACACAUUUACCAUAAAAUUUUUCACAGUCCUGGUUAAGGAAAUUGACAUUGGAACUUGAAACUUAGGUUUGAAUUUCUUAGCAACCUUGACAAAUCUGUGAUCUAACUAUCCUUGUCUAAUGGGAGGACAGAUACUGGUUUAUUUUCACCCCCUGAUUCUAAGGAAAACUUAUGACCCCAAUCGAUUAAAACAGGACUAAAAUUAAUGGAUAUGCAGAACUAUUUGUUAUUGAGUCCCAUGAAAGCCAAGGCAAAAUGGGACACACACCAGGUAUCAGAGUGAGGCAGCCCAGAGGUACGGCUUUCUCCCAGCCUGGCUGUAAACAGAGAUCAGCCUUGAAUAAAUGAUUCCUUGACGAACAUUUUCCAGUCCAGCUUGGUGAAAAAUUGAGAUCACUAUUGAGUGCCUAAAGGACAUGUUUUCUGCAUUGUUGACUGAAAGAAGAUUCCUAUACCAUAGUUACCUUGGUAUGUAGGUAGUAAAGACCUUGUACCAUUGGGUCAAAUGAGAACCUCACUUGUGGUCUUGUAUGAAGGGCUGUUCCAUCUCUAAGGGAAGGCCGUAAGUGGGGCCUGGAUAUUUCUGAGAAAACAUUUGAUGGUAGUACUCUAUUGAAGCCCCAAAUUCUAAGCUACAGAGCAGAAAAGACAACGUCUAGGAAAAGAGACACCAAGUGCCUACCCCUUUCACAGAAGAAUCUAGCUGCAGCUUCUGUAAUAUGUUUAUUUAGAAUCACAUCCCACCCUGCCCUAGUUCUCAAAUAAUCUAGUGUGGAUUUUAGACAAUUUUCUGUUGUCUAAGACAGAUCCCCAACCCCUACUCCACAGAUGGACCAGUAGUGGUCCAUGGCCUGUUAGGAACUGGGCCACACAGCAGGAGGUGAGCAGCGGGCAAAGGAUCAAAGCUUCAUCUGUAUUUACAGCCGCUCCCCAUUGCUCACAUUACCGCCUGAGCUCUGCCUCCUGUCAGAUCAGCAGCAGCAUUAGAUUCUCAUAGGAGCGCAAACCCUAUUGUGAACUGCACACGUGAGCAAUCUAGGUUACUCACUCCUUAUGAAAAUCUAAUACCUGAUGAUCUGUCACUGUCUCCCAUCACCCCCAGAUGGGACCAUCUAGUUGCAGGAAAACAAGCUCAGGGCUCCCACUGAUUCUAUAUAUUAUUGAGUUGUAUAAUUAUCUCAUUAUGUAUUACAGUGUAAUAAUAGAAAUUAAGUGCACAAUAAAGGUAAUGGUCUUGAGUCAUCCCAAAACCAUCCCCACACCACCCCAGUCCCUGGAAAAAUUGUCUUCCACAAAACCAGUCCCUGGUGCCUGAAAGGUUGGGGACUGCUAGUCUAUAAGAUGGUUUUCUAUUGCACAGUCCAGACUGACAAUGACAAGGAAUUUAGAAUCUCAGCUAUUGUUCUAUUUCCAGCAGCUCUUCCUAUUGAUUAACUAUGAGAAACAUAUUUUUAAGAAGGCUUAUUUUUGGGAAGUUAGAGUUGUGUUGUUUGAGGUGUGCUCCUGAAAGCUGUUUACUCAAACCUUUAUGGGUCAAGUUUUGUGCUGGGAGCAGGGUUUCCCUUGUAGUGAGGAGCUUACACCUGGAAACAUAGCAAAUGACGCAAUGGGAGAGCCACCUCACUGUGGAAUCAGGUAGGGCAUACAUACAGAAAUGAAUUUUAAAUGUUAAAGUAUUUCUAUUUUACACAAAUGAUCAUGUGAGGACUUAGAUUUUAUGAUAAAAAGUAAGGAAUAAAAUUUGAAAAAGCUUUAUAAGAACUUCUGGAAAACAAAAGCAAAAACAAGUCUCCCUGGUAUAAAGAUGCAUAUGCAGUGGAAGGAAAUGUACUGGGGUGGCAAUCGAGCAUCCUGGGAGGAGGAGAAGGGGCAAGAGUCAGAAUAAACAUAGGGCUCUGUCAUGUAUAGGUCUGAAGAAAAGAGGGCCGGUAUAUGGAUGAGCAUUUCGGGCCUUUUAACUACAGAGCUGGAAGAUAAUGCAGGUUCCCAGGAGGUAGGAUGACAAGGACAAAGGAGGGCAGGCCUGAACUAUUCAGGGGACGAGCUCUGGGCUGUUCUGAAUCGCAGAUGCCAUCCUGAAUUGCAUUUGUGUCAAAUAGGCUGCAGUGGUUCAUGCAUACCUUUGCUUCUGUUUGGCACACACCGUCUGAACCUCAGGCAUUUCUUAAGACUUUACCAAAACCAUUCAGUUUUCUUAUUGUAAAAUCGAGACACCACCACCUCUUCUGUCUCCCUUAGGGGGUUACGUGGGGGACCAAAUCCUUUUUUCUACCCUGGAGCAAGUGCCAGCACAGGGAGGUGGUAGAAAUGUUUGCUCAGGUGCCCACAGCCAAUUGAUGCCCCACUGCUCUUGUGUUUGUAUUGAAUCCCUUUGUUAAUUUUUUUCUUGUUUAGAGGAAAUACAUAUGGUGAUUUUGCAAUCAAUGCAGCAUUGCAUAAUAAUUAAAGGGCUAGCCUUGGGGCCAGACUAUUUCAGAUUCUAGCCCUCCCAUUUGCCUUGCAUGAUUACUUAUCUCAAGCUCAGUUUUCUCUUCUGUAAAACGGUUAUUUCUUACCAUGCUAUUAAGAGGACAGAAUGAGGUAAGGAUGACCCAAAUGUCAGUCCAUGUGCACUCAUUGAAUCUUAGGGUUUUUCCUCCCCUUCUUUGGUAUUUGUGCUCUUUGAAGAAAAGAGCACAUAUCUCCUCUUGAAAGAGGAGAUAUGUUGGGUUUUUGUUACUCUCUUCCACAAGAGGAGAUGUAAAAACUUUUCAAAAUUUUAUUUAGUAUUUCAGCUUGUGGAAAACACAUUAAGAUGGCAAAUAAUCUUAAAAUAAAUUAGUGGAGUUAAUGAUUUCCAAGUAGGGGGAACCCUAAUGAUUUAAAUAUGUCCCGAUGCUGUAUUAACUUACAGAGUGUAGCAUAGUGCCUGAGUUCAGAUUUAGGAGCCUACUGGCUGGACUCAGCACUUAUUAGCUGUGUGACCUUGGGCAAGUGAAUUAAUCUCUCUGUACCUCAGUUUUAUUAUUUAUACAACGUGGGUAGUAUUAGCACCUAGAUUUUGGGAUUGUUCCCCCAACCUCUACUCCAAAAUAGGGUUUUUUUGAGGUUUAAAUGAGUUAAUAUACAUUAAACCCUUAGAACCAUGCCUGGCCCUGUUUGCUGUUAUUUAUUAUUGUUAUGAUGCUGCUGCUGUAGUGUGAAUAAAGUCAAGAGUAAUUUAAGUUUUGAGAAAUACUUAAUUAUAAUAAAAUGUCUUUGGACAAGCAGUUAUAAGGAUUUUUUUUUCCCCCUGCAGGGCUCAAGUGUUUGAAAAGAAUCAAUGAACUGAGCCAUGUUCAAAUCCCUGUUAUGUUGAUGCCAGAUGACUUCAAAGCCUAUUCAAAAAUAAAGGUGGACAAUCACCUUUUUAACAAAGAAAACAUGCCGAGCCAUUUCAAGUUUAAGGAAUACUGCCCGAUGGUCUUCCGUAACCUGCGGGAGAGGUUUGGAAUUGAUGAUCAAGAUUUCCAGAAUUCCCUGACCAGGAGCGCACCCCUCCCCAACGACUCCCAGGCCCGCAGUGGAGCUCGUUUUCACACUUCCUACGACAAAAGAUACAUCAUCAAGACUAUUACCAGUGAAGACGUGGCCGAAAUGCACAACAUCCUGAAGAAAUACCACCAGUACAUAGUGGAAUGUCAUGGGAUCACCCUUCUUCCCCAGUUCUUGGGCAUGUACCGGCUUAAUGUUGAUGGAGUUGAAAUAUAUGUGAUAGUUACAAGAAAUGUAUUCAGCCACCGUUUGUCUGUGUAUAGGAAAUACGACUUAAAGGGCUCUACAGUGGCUAGAGAAGCUAGUGACAAAGAAAAGGCCAAAGAACUGCCAACUCUGAAAGAUAAUGAUUUCAUUAAUGAGGGCCAAAAGAUUUAUAUUGAUGACAACAACAAGAAGGUCUUCCUGGAAAAACUAAAAAAGGAUGUUGAGUUUCUGGCCCAGCUGAAGCUCAUGGACUACAGUCUGCUGGUGGGAAUUCAUGAUGUGGAGAGAGCCGAACAGGAGGAAGUGGAGUGUGAGGAGAACGAUGGGGAGGAGGAGGGCGAGAGCGAUGGCACCCACCCGGUGGGAACCCCCCCAGAUAGCCCCGGGAAUACACUGAACAGCUCACCACCCCUGGCUCCCGGGGAGUUCGAUCCGAACAUCGACGUCUAUGGAAUUAAGUGCCAUGAAAACUCGCCUAGGAAGGAGGUGUACUUCAUGGCAAUUAUUGACAUCCUUACUCAUUAUGAUGCAAAAAAGAAAGCUGCCCAUGCUGCAAAAACUGUUAAACAUGGCGCUGGCGCGGAGAUCUCCACCGUGAACCCAGAACAGUAUUCAAAGCGCUUUUUGGACUUUAUUGGCCACAUCUUGACGUAACCUCCUGCGCAGCCUCGGACAGACAUGAACAUUGGAUGGACAGAGGUGGCUUCGGUGUAGGAAAAAUGAAAACCAAACUCAGUGAAGUACUCAUCUUGCAGGAAGCAAACCUCCUUGUUUACAUCUUCAGGCCAAGAUGACUGAUUUGGGGGCUACUCGCUUUACAGCUACCUGAUUUUCCCAGCAUCGUUCUAGCUAUUUCUGACUUUGUGUAUAUGUGUGUGUGUGUGUGUUGGGGGGGGGUGAGUGUGUGCGCGCGUGUGCAUUUUAAAAGUCAUAAAUUAAUUAAAACAGAUCCACUUCGGUCAGUAUGUGUCCCAACAAAGACCCUUUGAUUCCAGCUAUGGCCGAAUGAAUGAGUGAGUGAGUGAGUGAGUGAAUGAACACACGUGUGGGGGAGGGGAGAAGGAAGUGCAUGAUGUCAGGCACCGUGUUGGCAUCACACAACAAACUGUGGAUCAGUUUUUUUUUUUUUUUUUUUUUUUUGGAGUUGAAAGAUGUGAGACAGUAUUCAGAAUAAUGAAGAUAAUAAUGAUGAUUAUUAUAAUAAUGAUGAUGAUUCCAAGGAAAAAACCUACAGCGAAUGUUCCAUUUCUACCCCGCACGCAGACACUCUCCCUAACACUGAUAACCUGAGCCCCCAGCACUGGACGGAAGAAUGCUGGCGUCUCCGUGUGUACUGGUUCAGGGUUCUGGCCCCAGCCUUGUCAGGACCCCCUGGUGUCCAGAGCCCCCACCCCUCCCGCAACAAGCAGCUGAUGCCCCAGUGAUUCUCUAUACAUUUUUCACCUCGGCCAAUAUGUCCAGGAAAACUGCUUACUUCUCUUUUCUUGCCUGGAGCCUUCAUUGUUCACCCUUACGUUGCAAUAUAGGAAUUAAUGCUACAAAAUAAAAGUAAAGCUUACCUGAAAAGUGCAUAGUUUGGGGCAAUGGUAUCUACAUCUCCCACUGUGGGAAAACCAGCAAAGCAUCAAAACUCUCAAUUCUCCUGUUACCAAAUGCAGAUCUGAAUUAUAAGAUGUUUAUGUUUGACCAUUGUUUCAACAAUGGGAUUUUGUUACGAAUUAUCCCUUUAACUGAAACCCUCAGUUUUACUGUUUACAUUAUUAGGAAAACAGGGAUAUCUUUUGAAUCUAAAAAUUUGAUGUACAGCAUGUGAUUUUUGAAGUUUACAUGUAAAGUCACAGUAUAGGUGAAAUAACGUUUGUCAUAUUUUGAGACGUAUCCUGCAGCCAUGUUUUUACGUGAGUGUUUUAGUCAAAGUACAUGGUAGACAGUCUUUCACAAUAAAAGGAAAAGGAUUUUUUUUUCCUCCAAAUGUACAUUUAUCAACCUAAUGAUUGAUUUUUUUAAAAAGAGAUUUCGCCCCAGUCUGGUUUAUGAAAGUUCAUUGCCCUAAACUGUGCUGAUUGUUUUUAAUCAAGUUAUAAAUUUCCAACCUAGAUCAUGUAUCUACCAACUCUCCUGCAUUUUCCAAAAGGCAUUGAGCUUAAAUAUUAGUCUUGCUUAGAGUAGGUUAUCCACUUACAUGCUGCGCUAAAGCCAUGCCUUUGAAACUCCUUGUUUAAAACAUGAUAUGAUUUUUGUGGGCAGUUUCAGAAAAGAAAACAAACAAACAAAAAUCGACCCUUUAAUUAUUACUUGCAACUCAACAGAUCUCCCUGCCGUACUGCCUUUUCCAGGAACUUUACUUCAGGGCUGUCCAGAUUGCAGCUGUGCCCCGUGUAUGUGGAUCUAGUUCACAGAGUCUUUGGAAGCCAGCAGUCGUGCCCUCCGUAUACUGUCCACUCAUUUUAUGUAGAUUUGGUAUCCUCAGCAGCCAGUGUUAACACCACUGUCACGUAGUGUACAGAUUCAUCUUUUAUGUAUUUAAAGUAAUCCAUACUAUGAUUUGGUUUUUCCCUGCACCAUUAAUUCUGGCAUCAGAUCAGUUUUUGUGUUGUGAAGUUCUACUGUGGUUUGACCCAAGACCACAACCAUGAGACCCUGAAGUAAAGAUAAGGUACACAUACAUUAUUUGAGUAACUGUUUCCUUGGGGGCCAAUCUGUGUAUGCUUUUAGAAGUUUACAGAAUGCUUUUAUUUUUGUCUAUAACAAACAGUCUGUCAUUUAUUUCUGUUGAUAAACCAUUUGGACAGAGUGAGGACGUUUGCCCUGUUAUCUCCUAGUGCUAACAAUACACUCCAGUCAUGAGCCGGGCUUUACAAAUAAAGCACUUUUGAUGACUCACAAGAUGAAUCCUUUUUUCCUCUGUCCCAAUUGUGUGUCUCUGUUCCAAACACAUUUUAAAUACUCGGUCCUGACAGUGUCUUUAGCUAAUCCUUGAAGAAAUGAAAGUGGAAUUGAA